UUUUUUUUUUUUUUUUUUUGAGAUGGAGUCUUACUCUGCCACCCAGGCUGGAGUGCACUGGUGUGAUCUUGGCUUACUGCAACCUCUGCCUCCCGGGUUCAAGCGAUUCUCCUGCCUCAGCCUCCCAAGUACCUGGGAUUACAGGCUCCCACCACCAUUCCUGGCUAGUUUUUGUAUUUUUAGUUUCACCAUGUUGGCCAGGCUGGUCUCAAACUCCUGAAAUCAGGUGAUCCACCCACCUCAGCCUCCCAAAGUGCUGGGAUUACAGGCGUGAGCCACUGCACCUGGCCCAGUUGAUGUCUUAUAAAGGAAAGUGCAGCAAAUGAGAUCCAAAGUACAAGUCAUCAUAAUUAGUAAUUGCCACUUGUUUUCCACUGAAAAUGGCAAAUUCUUCUCUGGGCUGUCAUUUUGUCUCCUAUAGACCAUAGAGGUUGUGAAGCUGAGGAUACUCUACUCCAACAUGGCCAACAUGGUACUGAUGGGUAGCUCUGUGAAAGGAGCAGAGACUGAAGGCGGAAGAAAUGUGGUACCACACCACGUCUUCUGCUUUUCACUACUUUAUUCCCUGUGUGCAAGGACAGAAAGACUUACAUGGUAAUUUUUUACAGUGAUUCUUAAAAAUUUUUAAAUUACAGACUUACAGAAAGGUUGCAGAGAUUACAAAGAACCUUUUUUCCCUGAGCUAUUUGAAAGUAAGCCACCAAAGUGAUGUCUUACUACUCCCAAAUAUUUCCUACAAACAAGGACUUUGUCCUACAUAACCAGAAUGCAACCAUCAAAAUCAGAAAAUUGACAUUGAUAAAUUACUACCCUCCAAUCCUCAGACCCCAGUUUUUCCAUCAGUUAUACUAAUAACAUUCUUUAUAGUUGAAGUAUCCAGUUGAGAAUCACACAGUACAUUUAGUUGUCAUGUUGCUUUAUUCUCCUUUAAUCUGGAACAUUUCCUCAGUUUUUUCUUGAAUUUCAUGAUCUUGAUACUUUUGAAGAUUACAGAACAGUUAUGUUGUAGAGUGUAUGUCAAUGACAUUUGUUUGAUGUUUCUUUGUGAUUAGAUUCAGGUUAUGCAGGAGUGUCGUGAAGCAAUGCUGCAUUCUCAUUGCAUCCUGUCAGGUGACACGUGAUUUCUAUUUAUCCCUUUAUGGUGAUGAUCACUUUGAUCACUUGAUUAAGGGAGUAUCUGGCAUUUCUAUUGUAAAAUAACUCUUUCCUCCUUUGUAAAUAAAAAGUACUUUGUGGGGAAGUUCUUUGAAACUUUGUAAAUAUCCCAGUCCUUAUCAAACUUUAUGUAAUUGAUUUAUUUGUAGUAACAUGGACUCAAUAUUUUCUUUGUUAUUCAAUGGGUUAUAAUUCAUUACUAUCAUUAUAUAUUUUGAUACUCCAGUUGUUCCUUAUUUAGUCAGUGACAUCCCCCUCAGGUUGGCUUCUGUGGCCUUUUGACAUGUCCCAUAACCCAUGACCUCUUUAUUGCUUUCAGGAACAAGUUGUUCUCGGCUUAUCUUGUAUUUUUCUUGCCCCAUCCCUGGAAUCAGCCAAUUUUACAAGGAUCCUUGGCUGUUUUUCAGUGGAGAAUGUUAUUUAAAAGCUAAGAUCUGAACUGGGCAUGGUGGCACACCUGUAAUCCCAGCACUUUGGGAGGCCCAGGUGGGAGAAUUGCCUGAGCCCAGGAGAGACCAGCCUGGGCAACAUAGCAAGAUCCUGUCUCUAUAUAAAUGCAUGAAUGAAUGCCAAGAUCUGGGUGCAGGGAGAACUCAUAGCUAGUGGGAUGCCACUGUUCUCAGGCCCUCUCAGAGGAAAAAGCUAGAAAAUAUAUAUGUUUAUGUACACACACACAGACACACACAUUCACAUGUAUACACACAUCUAAAUUUACAUCCAUUUCUCUCUAUAUUUUAAAAAACGAUGAGUUCCUGCUGACAUCUCCAGUUGCAAUUGUACAUCACAGGAUUCAUUCUAGUUUUCUCCUUUUCCCUAUUUUUCCCUCCCAUAUUCAACACUGUGAAACAUAAUUUGUUAUCCUUAAUAUAUUUACUACUUUGAUCAAUCCCCUAUAUGUGCUUAAUCUCCCAUUUCUGCCAUGCUGCCAUCCUUUCUUGCAUGAAUCUCUCGUCACCCCAUUUAGGUCCUAGCACUCCACACUUGGCUGCCCGCAAGUGAAUGCCUGUUACAUACCACUUUGGUUCUGACACCCUGGGCUGAGCUGCCUCUUCGCAGCCUCCUGGCUCUGACAUCUUCCUUGUUCACCGCCUAAUGGCUUUAAGACUGAAUUGCUCAGGAAAGGGAAGAUAAGCAACGAUGUGCUGAGCUGAAGAAAGCCUUGUGUACUGCCCAUGAGAAGUUCUGUUUCUGGCCAGACAGCCCAUCCCCAGACCGAUUUGGGAUGUUGCCCCUGGAUGAGCCUGCUAUUCUUGUUAGUGAAUUCCUAGAUCGUUUUCAAAGCCUUUGUCACUUGGACCUCCAGCUUCCUUCCCUAAGGCCGGAGGACUUGAAAACUAUGUGCUUGACAGAAGACAAGAUCAGUCUUCUCCUACACUUGCUUGAAGAUGAACUUGAUCACCGAACUGAUGAGAGAAAAACUACAAUCAAAUUAGGCUCAGACAUCCAAGUCCACGUCACUGCCUGUAUUCUCUCUGUGUGUGGCUGGGCGUGUAGUUCCUCUUUGGAAUCCAUGCAGCUCUCCCUGAUAACAUGUUCGCAAUGUAUGAGGAAGGUGGGGCUCUGGGGCUUCCAGCAGAUUGAAUCGUCCAUGACUGACCUGGAUGCAUCCUUUGGCCUGACCAGCUCCCCAAUCCCAGGCCUUGAGGGGCGACCAGAGCGCUUACCUCUGGUGCCUGAAUCUCCUCGGAGGAUGAUGACCCGGAGCCAGGAUGCCACUUUCUCCCCAGGCUCAGAGCAGGCUGAAAAGAGCCCUGGUCCCAUUGUCUCUCGAACUCGGAGCUGGGACUCUUCCAGUCCUGUUGACCGUCCUGAGCCAGAGGCUGCUAGCCCCACCACCAGAACUCGCCCAGUGACCCGAAGCAUGGGAACAGGAGACACCCCUGGCCUGGAGGUACCAUCUAGCCCUCUGCGGAAAGCCAAGCGAGCUCGCCUCUGCUCCUCCAGCAGUUCGGACACAUCUUCCCGAAGCUUCUUUGAUCCCACCUCUCAGCAUAGAGACUGGUGCCCUUGGGUGAAUAUCACACUUGGCAAAGAAAGCAGGGAGAAUGGUGGAACUGAACCAGAUGCCAGCGCCCCAGCAGAGCCAGGCUGGAAAGCAGUGCUGACCAUCCUCUUGGCGCACAAACAGUCUAGCCAGCCAGCUGAAACGGACUCCAUGAGUCUCUCUGAGAAAUCAAGGAAAGUAUUCCGAAUAUUUCGGCAGUGGGAAUCUCUGUGCUCAUGCUGAAGAUACUCCAGCGCCUUCCUGGAGAUAGCUGGAAUGAGAGUGACUUUUUGAAAAAUUAAGGCUGAGUUCCUUUCGGUCAGCUGACACUAAGUUUUUCCUGUUCUGGGUUAAUCAUAAGGAGCCCCCUGCCAUAGCAAAGGCAGUGAGUGUCAACUAUCUGCAUCUGGCUGAGAGAGACCCGUUUCCUUUCAGGGAUGUGGACAGGGUAAGGGCAGCAAGCAUGGUUCUGUUAAAGGAGUGUGGGAUUAACAGACUAGAAGGAAGACUAAGGACCUGACCACCCAUUUCAGCAUCUUCAAUGUGGAGCAGUGUUCUGAGGACUCUUCUAUCCUAGGACUAUGACAGUGUGUAUUAAUAAAAUAUUUGCUAAGAUUCUCA